AGCGCCCUGCACCGCAGGCCCAGCGCUCGCCCCACCGAAAUUGCCGAACCUGGUUCACACACUCAUUUACUCAUUCCGCAGAUAGGUCUGAGGGCCUCCCAUGGGCCACGCGCUGGGGAUUCAAGGUGGCUGGGACAUUCCCCUGCUCUAGAGGCGCUCGCAAGUUAGCGGGGACACCGUUACCGCAAUUACAACACAAUGUAGCAAGUGCUUCUACCAGGUGCCUGCUGAGAUCAUGCCAGCAAGCAUGUUCUGCCUGGAUGACCUAGGGCCCCACAUUGAACUGGGGCCUGGGGGAUGCAUAAGUUUGUCACGUAAGGGGCAUGUGCAAGAAUGGAAGAUGUGCAAAAAAGGGAGGAGGAGGCAUUUCACGGAGAAGGAAACGGAGUGGAAGCAGCCUGAGGCCCUCAUCCAAUGCAGAUGUCUGUGCCGUGCGUCUUGUCCAGCCUGCAGAACCAUGAGCCAAAUAAACCUCUUUUCACUACCCAAUCUCAGCUCUUAUCAAAGGUGCUGGAAGUGCUUGAUCCUGACCGGAAGCUGGAGGACACAUGGGCUUAUUGUCAGGACACCAGGAAAGGAAUGAAGGAACCCACGAAGCUUUUAAAAAAACAUUCUACCCAAGUCUACCUGGGACCUUCCAAGAAGACGUCUGUGUCAAACGCAGGCCAAUGGCUUUAUGAAGAAAAGCCACAUAAAAUGGAUUUGCUCCAUGAAAAUGGUCCUCGUCCUGGUCUUCAUGAAAAUGUAUGCAAAGCAGUUAGUGACUUCUGCAAGUGGGUUACUACUUUUGGAAUUUCGGACAUCGAUGAAGAGUUCAUCUUGAAACAGUUUGACAUUGACUAUGAGACCAAACCAAGCCAUGAUGCGCUCCACACGAUGAAGCUAAAUCAGGUUCCUCUGGAGCUAAAGCGUAGUGUGGGGCUCAGUAAACUGCAGGAGACAGAGUUCUUCCAGAAACUAGGCUAUGAGAGGAAACUCCAGAAACCACAGAAUCCUUAUAAGCCAAAGUGGGUGAAGAUGAGGUAUGGAGCAUGGUAUUUGAACCCCAAGUUGUGGAAAAAGCAAAGAGUAGACGAGCCUCUGGUUGACCCUGAGGUCUCACAUAAGGCUCAAGAGGAGAAUUUUAAAAAGGAGCUGCAGGAACAGGAGGAGUUACUUGCAGACCUUCACGGAACAGUUGCCUUUAAGGAUUUCAUUCUAAGCAGGGGCUACAGGACGCCACGUUUCCUUGAGAAUAUGUAUAUCGGGAAGGAAUGUAAACGUGCAUGUAAUAAGACUCCUAUAAAACGAACUCAAGCAUAGAAGAAUCGUAGGAGAAUGAUUAGGCAGAUUUUAUUACUACGUACUUGGCUAUUUCUCUGUCUCCUUUUAAAGAUUAAACAGAGUUUAUGAUGAGUGUCCCACUGUGGAUGUUCAACUUUGACUUGGCAACAUCUGUAAAUGUAAUACCUGAUGGUUAUAAGCAUUUCUCAAUGGAUUUCUGCUUCAGUUAAUCAACAUUUUGUAUACUUUAUCACCCAUGAGAUCAAUAUUCACAUGUAAUCUUCUCAUAUUUUUGUGGCACGUGAAUAUUAUAUAGGUAUAUCAACUAUUGGUAAAAAUAAAUAAAGGCAUAAAUAAAAACAGA